CCUAAGCUACUGCACACUAAACAGUGAGAGAGCUUUUCCCUGCAGUCUUGUUGAAGCACCCCGGGUUUUUUGCUCAUUGUUGGUGGGUGCAUUUUAAUUUUUUCAUUCCCUGGACUAUGGGUUAUGAUAUCCAUACUCACUGAAGACAAAAAGCCACCUUUUCUGCGUCUUGGUGGCAUGCAUGUGUCUCAUCAUCCUUUCAAACUUGUGGUGGAACAGGGUUUUCUUCCCUGUCUGUGUAUUUUGAGCCAGCACAGUUACCAAAAUUGAACUUGUCUUUCGCUUGUGAGCGGUUGUGGUCAUUGUGAGGGCGGGUCAUGAGGAGGCUGUAGCCAAGGACGAGGUGUGUGCGGCUGUUGCCUGGACGUUUGUCCAAUCCACGUUGACAUUUGAGGGAUCACAGCGUGUGAAAAUGAACUCAGAGGAGAAUUGGUGAAUUCCUAUCCAGUGGGCAUCUUCAAACCCUGGUCGACGGCGGAAGAAUAUCAGGUCCUGAGAUCACCCACCCGGCGCGGCAACAGUGCAGAGUGGCCACAUCUGGUGGAAGAAGAAAAAAAUGUAGUUAUUGAAUUCAAUCAAGUGUUUGCAUCUUUCAAGCUAUCAACAAAAUUCCAUCAAGAAAGGUUCCAGUUGGUCUCACAGACGUAUGGAUAUCCGAGGAGCCACCUAAAGAUGGAGAAAUCAAGGCAUAGAGAGAUUAAGUGACUUUGCCACAGUCACAAGCUGGAGAGGACCAGGAGUAGAGCUUAGAGCGAGCCCCUGACUCUGGGCCUGCGUCCUGCCAGGAGUCACGCUGCCUCCGUUCCUAGGAGAGAAGACUUCCUGUAAGAUGGAGGUGGACACCGAGGAGAAGCGGCAUCGCACGCGGUCCAAAGGGGUUCGAGUUCCCGUGGAACCAGCCAUACAAGAGCUGUUCAGCUGUCCCACCCCUGGCUGUGACGGCAGUGGUCAUGUCAGUGGCAAAUAUGCAAGACACAGAAGUGUAUAUGGUUGUCCCUUGGCGAAAAAAAGAAAAACACAAGAUAAACAGCCCCAGGAACCUGCUCCUAAACGAAAGCCAUUUGCCGUGAAAGCAGACAGCUCCUCAGUGGAUGAGUGUGACGACAGUGAUGGGACUGAGGACAUGGAUGAGAAGGAGGAGGAUGAGGGGGAGGAGUACUCCGAGGACAAUGAUGAGCCAGGGGAUGAGGACGAGGAGGACGAGGAGGGGGACCGGGAGGAGGAGGAGGAGAUCGAGGAGGAGGAUGAGGACGAUGACGAGGAUGGAGAAGAUGUGGAGGAUGAAGAAGAGGAAGAGGAGGAGGAGGAGGAGGAGGAAGAGGAAGAAGAAAACGAAGACCAUCAAAUGAAUUGUCACAAUACUCGAAUAAUGCAAGACACAGAAAAGGAUGAUAACAAUAAUGACGAAUAUGACAAUUACGAUGAACUGGUGGCCAAGUCAUUGUUAAACCUCGGCAAAAUCGCUGAGGAUGCAGCCUACCGGGCCAGGACUGAGUCAGAAAUGAACAGCAAUACCUCCAAUAGUCUGGAAGACGAUAGUGACAAAAACGAAAACCUGGGUCGGAAAAGUGAGUUGAGUUUAGACUUAGACAGUGAUGUUGUUAGAGAAACAGUGGACUCCCUUAAACUAUUAGCCCAAGGACACGGUGUUGUGCUCUCAGAAAACAUGAAUGACAGAAAUUAUGCAGACAGCAUGUCGCAGCAAGACAGUAGAAAUAUGAAUUACGUCAUGUUGGGGAAGCCCAUGAACAACGGACUCAUGGAAAAGAUGGUGGAGGAGAGCGAUGAGGAGGUGUGUCUGAGCAGUCUGGAGUGUUUGAGGAAUCAGUGCUUCGACCUGGCCAGGAAGCUCAGUGAGACCAACCCGCAGGAGAGGAAUCCGCAGCAGAACAUGAACAUCCGUCAGCAUGUCCGGCCAGAAGAGGACUUCCCCGGAAGGACGCCGGACAGAAACUACUCGGACAUGCUGAACCUCAUGCGGCUGGAGGAGCAGUUGAGCCCCCGGUCGAGAGUGUUUGCCAGCUGUGCGAAGGAGGAUGGGUGUCAUGAGCGGGACGACGAUACCACCUCUGUGAACUCGGACAGGUCUGAAGAGGUGUUCGACAUGACCAAGGGGAACCUGACCCUGCUGGAGAAAGCCAUCGCUUUGGAAACGGAAAGAGCAAAGGCCAUGAGGGAGAAGAUGGCCAUGGAAGCUGGGAGGAGGGACAAUAUGAGGUCAUAUGAGGACCAGUCUCCGAGACAACUUCCCGGGGAGGACAGAAAGCCUAAAUCCAGUGACAGCCAUGUCAAAAAGCCAUACUAUGGUAAAGAUCCCUCAAGAACAGAAAAGAAAGAGAGCAAGUGUCCAACCCCCGGGUGUGAUGGAACCGGCCACGUAACUGGGCUGUACCCACAUCACCGCAGCCUGUCCGGAUGCCCGCACAAAGAUAGGGUCCCUCCAGAAAUCCUUGCCAUGCAUGAAAGUGUCCUCAAGUGCCCCACUCCGGGCUGCACGGGGCGCGGGCAUGUCAACAGCAACAGGAACUCCCACCGAAGCCUCUCCGGAUGCCCGAUCGCUGCAGCAGAGAAACUGGCCAAGGCACAGGAAAAGCACCAGAGCUGCGACGUGUCCAAGUCCAGCCAGGCCUCGGACCGCGUGCUCAGGCCAAUGUGCUUUGUGAAGCAGCUGGAGAUUCCUCAGUAUGGCUACAGAAACAAUGUCCCCACAACUACGCCGCGUUCCAACCUGGCCAAGGAGCUCGAGAAAUAUUCCAAGACCUCGUUUGAAUACAACAGUUACGACAACCAUACUUAUGGCAAGCGAGCCAUAGCUCCCAAGGUGCAAACCAGGGAUAUAUCCCCCAAAGGAUAUGAUGAUGCGAAGCGGUACUGCAAGGACCCCAGCCCCAGCAGCAGCAGCACCAGCAGCUACGCGCCCAGCAGCAGCAGCAACCUGAGCUGCGGCGGGGGCAGCAGCGCCAGCAGCACGUGCAGCAAGAGCAGCUUCGACUACACGCACGACAUGGAGGCGGCCCACAUGGCGGCCACCGCCAUCCUCAACCUGUCCACGCGCUGCCGCGAGAUGCCGCAGAACCUGAGCACCAAGCCGCAGGACCUGUGCGCCACGCGGAACCCUGACAUGGAGGUGGAUGAGAACGGGACCCUGGACCUCAGCAUGAACAAGCAGAGGCCGCGGGACAGCUGCUGCCCCAUCCUGACCCCUCUGGAGCCCAUGUCCCCCCAGCAGCAGGCAGUGAUGAACAACCGGUGUUUCCAGCUGGGCGAGGGCGACUGCUGGGACUUGCCCGUAGACUACACCAAAAUGAAACCCCGGAGGAUAGACGAGGACGAGUCCAAAGACAUUACUCCAGAAGACUUGGACCCAUUCCAGGAGGCUCUAGAAGAAAGACGGUAUCCCGGGGAGGUGACCAUCCCAAGUCCCAAACCCAAGUACCCUCAGUGCAAGGAGAGCAAAAAGGACUUAAUAACAUGUCCAACUCCAGGGUGUGAUGGGAGUGGUCAUGUGACUGGUAAUUACGCCUCACACAGAAGUCUGUCUGGCUGCCCCCUGGCGGACAAAAGCAUUCGAAGUAUGCUGGCCACCAGCUCCCAAGAACUCAAGUGCCCCACGCCUGGCUGUGAUGGUUCUGGACAUAUCACCGGCAAUUAUGCUUCUCAUCGGAGCCUUUCAGGUUGCCCAAGAGCAAAGAAAAGUGGUAUCAGGAUAGCACAGAGCAAAGAAGAUAAAGAAGAUCAAGAACCCAUCAGGUGUCCGGUCCCCGGGUGCGACGGCCAGGGCCACAUCACUGGGAAGUACGCGUCCCAUCGCAGCGCCUCCGGGUGCCCCUUGGCGGCCAAGAGGCAGAAAGACGGGUACCUGAAUGGCUCCCAGUUCUCCUGGAAGUCGGUCAAGACGGAAGGCAUGUCCUGCCCCACGCCAGGAUGCGACGGCUCAGGCCACGUCAGCGGCAGCUUCCUCACACACCGCAGAUAUGGUAUUUUCAACUUAAGAUGGCUUUAUGGGGAUGCUGACCCCAUGGUAUGUGGAGGAGUACCUGUAUCCAUCCCCAUGGUAUGUGGAGGAGCACCUGUAUCCAUCCCCGUGGUAUAUGGAGGAGCACCUGUAUCCAUCCCCGUGGUAUGUGGAGGAGCACCUGUAUCCAUCCCCGUGGUAUGUGGAGGAGUACCUGUAUCCAUCCCCGUGGUAUGUGGAGGAGUACCUGUAUCCAUCCCCGUGUUAUGUGGAGGAGUACCUGUAUCCAUCCCCGUGGUAUGUGGAGAAGUACCUGUAUCCAUCCCCAUGGUAUGUGGAGGAGUACCUGUAUCCAUCUCCGUGGUAUGUGGAGGAGUACCUGUAUCCAUCCCCGUGGUAUGUGGAGGAGUACCUGUAUCCAUCCCCGUGGUAUGUGGAGGAGUACCUGUAUUCACACUGUUGUGGAACUGAUCUCUCCAAUUCUUCCGUCUCCAUUGAAACACUGUCUCCAUUCAACACUGACUCGCCCUUCCUCAGCUGCCUAGCCCCUGGCACCCACACUGUGCUUUCUGCCUCUGUGAAUCUGAUGCUUCUAGGGACCUCCUAUAAGUAGAAUCCCAUGGGGUUUGCUUUUUUGUGACCGUCCUAUUUCAUGGAGCCCCAUGUCCUCAAGGUUGUAGCACGUAUCCAAGCUUCCUUCCCUUUUGAGACUGAAUAAUAUUCCAUCAUGUGUUGACUAUGGUUUUUCUCUGUUGAGCAAGCCUUCAUCAAUUUUAAUAGAUAGGCAGAAUAUUAUUUUCUGAAAGUGUAAUAAUAUGAAUACCCAGCAAGAACACAGCUAAGCGCACAGAAAUACACUCAUUAGGAAGUCUUAGACAUUUCUCUUUCCUUGGAAGCCCUGGCCUUGCCCAGACUGCCAGGACUGCCUGGUGGUUUUCCCAAACCUGGUUAGCAGGAGCCUCCCACAAAGCCCCCGCGGGCACGUCAAGAUUGGAGUUUGGAGGGCCCCUGUGCAUCCCACCCACUGCGCAAACAAAGCAGCGGUUAGAAGCAGCAGCAAGAACAGAUUGAAAUAGAAGUUGCCUGUUUUAUUUCUCUUUUACCCCAAACUGUGACAAUCUAGCCAGAUGAUGAAGAACUGCUUUCAAGCAGGUGCCAAAAUAGAAACAGUAGAGGAAGCAGGAACCAAUGCCCAUGGUUUGGGGCCCUGCUCACAUGCCCAGCCCACUCCCGGCCCCGGGUCUCAGACCUGACAGGAGCCCCUGGCCAUCCACCCCAUUUGCUGUGAAAUCGUUUCCACUUCACUUCAUGGGGAGUCCUGGCGCAGCCGCUGCUCUUUCUGCGUUGAGGGUUAGGCAGGAGGGCUCCUUUCCCCGAUCCUGCUCCCUGAGCUGAGUCGUGUCUGAAAAAAGCAGAACUGAUGUAAGAGAAAUAGAAAACAUUUUAUCUUUAGGGUUGGCAAGGUCUUUCUAGAAAAGCAGUGUCUAAGAUGAAAAGUCAAGGCCCCAUCCCGGCUCCUGGGCACACACAUACGUGGUGCCAUGACCUUUGGGGAAGAUGCCAUGUUGUGAUUGUAAAAGCAGCUAUCAUGAGACCCUCAGGUCAGGUGUAAAGGCCAAUCCCUCCCAGAAAGGAGGGGGAGAACUGGAGGCACAUGGAGAAGCCCAGGACGGAGGAGUCAGGGAGAAUUCUACAACGACAGAAGUCAGGUAGAAAAUGUUGAUUGUAUACAUGAGGAAGCAGCAGAGCGGACAGCUCAGGACAGGAAGGUGUCCUCAGUCCCGGUGAACACAGACUGAGGACAGUACCAGGCCAUGACCAGGGACCAUGAGGCCCAUGCAGACCCCCAGCAAGCGUUCUGGACAGGUGCUAAGGCCAAGCCACAUAGCAGACGCAGCAGAGCCUAGGGUGGUGAUGGUGAGUAAGACCUAACACUCACUCCCCGAGCCCAGAACCUCACAGUGAGGGAACAGACUCACAUAAGAGCCUCGGAUGCGGGCACUGGGGCAAGGCCAACCACGGGACAGAUGCAAUGCCACUGGCACACACUGUGGGGGACACUGGCUUUACACUCAGAGAAAUCUGAGGAGGCUUCCUAGGAACUUGAGACCCUUGGGGUCUGUGCCCGAGGAGAGCUCAACCUGCAGCUCACCCUCCCCCUAAGCCGCCGACAGACGUGUCAUUCAUUCAUCUCAUUCGGCCGACACAGACAGACAUGCCUCCACCAGCACCGAUGAUCUCCGUCCAGGUCUGGUUUACAAAGUUGAGUACCGUGGCCUGCUCUUUAGAGGAGAGAAGAGACCAUCUUUUAGAGAAUGCUGUGGACUGGGGUGAAGGAGAUUACAGAUGCUGCAACAUGGUGCCAGGCCAGCGAUCAGCAACACAGAGGAGAAAUGUCUAGUCCAGAUGGGGUGAACAGGCCAGGGCCCUUCAGGAGCCAAGACAGGAGCUGAAUUUUGAAAAAAGGCACAGCUCACCACAGGGAGGAAGGUUACAUUGAGGGCUUUAAGUGACUCUUGGAGUCCGGGCUUUGAAUGCACCACCUUGGUGGCCGCGGAGGAGAGCUGGAAUGGACGGGCAGGCAGACACGUUGAGCCGUUCCUGCAGACCUAAGCGAGGCAUGAUGAGGGCUAGACCUCCAACAUGAAAGGAAGGACAGAUUAGAGGACUGUUUAGGAAACAGAAUGAGCAGGGCCUUGUGGGUGAAUCCCGGCAGGAGAGGUGGCCCCAGCCCCAGCAGCUGCACGGGUGGCAAUGCUGGCAGUUGGGAACACAAGGAAAGAAUGAAGCCUUGAACGCCAUGGGUAUCUUAGUCUGCUCAGCCGUCACAACAGAAUACCCUAGGCCAGGUGGCUUGAGCAACUGACCUCUAUCCCCUGUCCCUGGGCUGGAAGUCUGAGAUCAGGUUCCAGCUGAUCUGGUUUCUGGGGAGGCCUCUCUUCCUGGUUGGCAGACAGGGGCCUUCUCACUGUGUCCUCACAAGGCAGGGAGAGAGCAGGCUCGCUGGCAUCUCCUCUCAUAAGGACUCUGAUCCCAUCAGAUCAGGACCCCACCCUUACAAGCCCAUUUACAUGAAUUAUUCCCUUAGAGGCCCCAGCUCCAAACACACCCAGGGGUUAGGGCUUCAACACAGGAACCUCGAGGGACACAAAUACUCACACCAUAAAAGUGGGGAAAGAUGGUUAUUUCAUUUUAAAUACGUGAACUUGAGAUUCUGUGGGACUUUGAAGGGGGAAUAUCCACCAAGCAGCUGGUAACGGGCCUCGGGAAGUGUCUGAGGAGAGCCGCGUAGGAAUCGGAAAUCAGCAGCACUCAGGUCACACUUGACCCUGCAGGUUCACCCCGGGACUCAGGGGUCCAGGGGGAAGAGCAUCAGCAAAGACACCCCUGGGAGACACACACGUUUUGUGACAGGUGGAGGCGGAGAGGCCGUGAUGAAGACAGAGUUGCAUGGUGGCAUUAGGGGAGCCAGGCGCCAUGAUGUGCAGAAGCUUCCAGAGAAAAGAACACACACAAUACUGGGAAAGUGGCGAGAGGCCGGUGUGGCGGAGAGUUCAAAACGAUGCUGGGCUCAUUUGGGGCAUUGGCCGUGGGAAUACAACUGAGGCACUUUGUGGAGAGUUUAGGGAAAAGAUCAGGCACCAAAACCAGACUGAGAUAGGACGAGAGUCAGAUGGAAAGUUCAGGGGGUUGUAGAGGACAUGACUAAUGGUUCUAGAAAUGCAGACCAGACGAGAGGGGAGGAACGACGUUGGCAGUAGCUGGAAAGGCGCAGAAGUGGGCAGGACCUCACAGGCAGAGAGAAAUGUGGGUCUGGAAUUUAUCUGAAGAGGAGAAACCAGGAGGAAGAAAUGGUUUAAAGAUACAGAAGGCAGCAGGAGUACCAGGUGGAGACAGAUCUUGGUGGAGGUCAGGAAGCCACAGACAAGCUGGACAAAUGUGGCUGUAACUGCACUGGGGAGCUGGGGGUCCUCAGAGCAGAGCUCCAUCUGGGGGGAGCCAGGGGUCCUCGGAGCAGAGCUCCAUCUGCUCCAUCUGGACAAGGACUUCAUGGGAGUCAUUCACACACGCGUCGGGCACCCGAGUGGGGUUGCAGGGUGUGGUGGUGUCUGGGACACCUUCAGGAGAGGGGAUUCCAAGGGAAUCACGGCCAUGCCAAGGACACACAGGGAAUUGGAGACCACGUGUUGGCCACUGGAGGGAAGGGCACACUUUUGUCCCCAACACUCAGCUGUCAGGAUGUGGGGAAGACAGCAGCGUGGGAGCCUUACUCCAGCCCCAUUGACAUGCAGGUGCAUGCGGGAGGUGCAGAGGGAGCAGCUCCAGGCCACCAGCCACCAAGGGGCUGUGGAAUUUGGAGGAUCCUGUGAGGGAGGCCGCAGCCAGCCAGCAGGCGAGGACAGAGCGAGAAGGCACACUCCACAGUUCCCCUAGGCCCAGGGAAGAGGCUCCUGAGGGAAGGACUCCUGCCACCCUCCACAGUUCCCCAGGCCUGGCCUUCCUCCUGUCUCUGGGAGCAUCUCCUCCUAGCCAUCCCAAGCUGCCUCAUCCCCAUGGUGUUUCACACCUGUGAGCCCUUUGGGGUGCCAAGAGCACCCUUUCCCACAUCUCCCUGUGAGCCCUUCCAGGUGCCGAGAAUACCCUUUCCCCCAUCUCCCUGUGAGCCCUUCCGGGUGCCGAGAACACCCUUUCCUCCAUCUCCCUGUGAGCCCUUCGGGGUGCCGAGAACACCCUUUCCUCCAUCUCCCCAUCUGCCAUGUGAUGCCUCCUUAUCUUCCAGACAAUGUCAGUGGAGGCUGUUCAGGACUUAUUAUGGGCCAGACAGAGCUCUAAGCACCUCCGCAUACCAACCUUCUUAAUCCUCACAGCAGCCUGAAGAAAUGGGCUCUGUAAUUAUCCCUGUUUUAAAGAUCAGGACAUUGAGGCAAAGAGAAGAGAACUUCCUGCCUGGGGUCCUGUGAGUGACGGAGCCAGGGCUCAGGUCCAGGCUGCCUGACCCCCCGUGAGUGACUCCUUUCCACUAUCUCAUCUCUCCCUGACUCCGAUCCCUGUGAUGAUCUUGGUGAAACUGCCCCAGCCUCCUCUCUGCAGACACUGUCCCUUCUCUUUCUACCCGAUACUAAGUAGCUGCUACAUCUGUCAUGCUCCAUUGCAAUGUCUGUGCGUGGGGACCUUUGUUCCUUCCUGCACAUCUGGGGCACCUCGCUCGGCGCUGCACACACAGCUCCUAAGAAAAGUUUUCCUGCACCAUUGACUCAAUACAUUUUAUAAGAGGAGAUUUAAGUCUGUGUUGAAACAGGAAGCAGCCAUGUGUUCGCUGGGUGCAGAUGUGAGGAACCUAGGGCCUGCCAGGAGACAGGUGCAAUUCACAGGUGUAUGGGAGGGUCAAUUCACAGGUGUAUGGGAAGGUCAAUUCACAGGUGUAUGGGAAGGUCAAUUCACAGGUGUAUGGGAGGGUCAAUUCACAGGUGUAUGGGAAGGUCAAUUCACAGGUGUAUGGGAGGGUCAAUUCACAGGUGUAUGGGAGGGUCAAUUCACAGGUGUAUGGGAGGGUCAGUUCACAGGUGUAUGGGAGGGUCAGUUCACAGGUGUAUGGGAGGGUCAGUUCACAGGUGCAUGGGAGGGUCAAUUCACAGGUGCAUGGGAGGGUCAGUUCACAGGUGCAUGGGAGGGUCAGUUCACAGGUGUAUGGGAGGGUCAGUUCACAGGUGUAUGGGAGGGUCAGUUCACAGGUGUAUGGGAGGGUCAGUUCACAGGUGUAUGGGAGGGUCAGUUCACAGGUGUAUGGGAGGGUCAGUUCACAGGUGUAUGGGAGGGUCAGUUCACAGGUGUAUGGGAGGGUCAGUUCACAGGUGUAUGGGAGGGUCAGUUCACAGGUGUAUGGGAGGGUCAGUUCACAGGUGUAUGGGAGGGUCAGUUCACAGGUGUAUGGGAGGGUCAGUUCACAGGUGUAUGGGAAGGUUGGAAGGUGAGAGAUUCUAGUCCAGCAAAAGAAGUCAGGAGGUAAAGUUGGGGGAGAAGGAACCAGGGAGUGCUCUGCCCAGUCCUCAGCACCCCCAGAGGUGAGAGGCCCAACGCCAUCUUCAUGGGAGAUCCUCACCAAGCGCUGGGCAGCCAGUAGAUGCAGGGAGGAUGGGGCAGAAGAGGGAGGGAAGUGGAGGUUCCUCUGCAGCUGUUGAGACUUCUCUCUCAUGUGCAGUGCCCUGAGCAUCCUUUUUUGCCACCACUUCAGUUCUCACUCCACUUCAGUGAAAUUUAAGAAGAGUCUCCAAACUUAAAGUUCUAACUCUGAAAAACAAGUAUUUUUAGAAGUAACUCAUAUCUUAAGAGUCUCGUCCACCAUACAUUUUUUUAAAGUCCUUCCCUAGGCCCUCUUAAAACCUUUUCUGUCUGGAACAUGUGAAUUGUUCUAUUUAUUUUUUGGUUCCUCUCUAGUCCAUUAUAAAUGAGAACAUAACCUUUUAUAGAAUGUUUGUCUUGCUUGAUAUAUCUCAAGGGAAUUGUUGCAAAAAUAAAUCACCAUAUUGAGUACUUA